ACACCCAGGCCGGCAAAGAGCAGGUAUCAGCACUGCAAGCACCAAGUGUGUCUUGAGCUCAGUGAGUACUGGGUAUGUGUCACAUUGCCAAAUCCCGGAUCACAAGUCUCCAUGAACUGCUGGUGAGCUAGGAUAAUAAAACCCCUGACAUCACCAUUCCAGAAGCUUCACAAGACUGCAUAUAUAAGGGGCUGGCUGUAGCUGCAGCUGAAGGAGCUGACCAGCCAGCUGACCCCUCACACUCACCUAGCCACCAUGGACAUCGCCAUCCACCACCCCUGGAUCCGCCGCCCCUUCUUUCCUUUCCACUCCCCCAGCCGCCUCUUUGACCAGUUCUUCGGAGAGCACCUGUUGGAGUCUGAUCUUUUCCCGACGUCUACUUCCCUGAGUCCCUUCUACCUUCGGCCACCCUCCUUCCUGCGGGCACCCAGCUGGUUUGACACUGGACUCUCAGAGAUGCGCCUGGAGAAGGACAGGUUCUCUGUCAACCUGGAUGUGAAGCACUUCUCCCCAGAGGAACUCAAAGUUAAGGUGUUGGGAGAUGUGAUUGAGGUGCAUGGAAAACAUGAAGAGCGCCAGGAUGAACAUGGUUUCAUCUCCAGGGAGUUCCACAGGAAAUACCGGAUCCCAGCUGAUGUAGACCCUCUCACCAUUACUUCAUCCCUGUCAUCUGAUGGGGUCCUCACUGUGAAUGGACCAAGGAAACAGGUCUCUGGCCCUGAGCGCACCAUUCCCAUCACCCGUGAAGAGAAGCCUGCUGUCACCGCAGCCCCCAAGAAAUAGAUGCCCUUUCUUGAAUUGCAUUUUUUAAAACAAGAAAGUUUCCCCACCAGUGAAUGAAAGUCUUGUGACUAGUGCUGAAGCUUAUUAAUGCUAAGGGCAGGCCCAAAUUAUCAAGCUAAUAAAAUAUCAUUCAGCAACAGAUAACUGUCUUGUGUUUGAAUAUUCCACACACUUUUAAAUAAAUAUACAGAUACCACAGA